GAGUCUGUGCGAAGGUCCGUGGACAGACUGCUUUGCCUGUUGUUGCUCUUCGGAGGCGGCGAUCCCCGAAGGCGAGCUGAAAUACGGCUGCAGGCUACAAUUUGCAGCCGACCAUUAUGGAUGACAAGGAGCCGAAGAGGUGGCCCACCCUCAGGGACCGCUUGUGCUCGGAUGGCUUCUUAUUUCCCCAAUACCCCAUUAAACCGUAUCAUCUGAAGGGGAUCCACAGAGCUGUCUUCUAUCGUGAUCUGGAGGAACUGAAGUUCGUUCUGCUCACGCGUUAUGACAUCAAUAAGAGAGACAGGAAGGAAAGGACCGCCCUACAUUUGGCCUGUGCCACUGGCCAACCGGAAAUGGUACAUCUCCUGGUGUCCAGAAGAUGUGAGCUUAACCUCUGCGACCGUGAAGACAGGACACCUCUGAUCAAGGCUGUACAACUGAGGCAGGAGGCUUGUGCAACUCUUCUGCUGCAAAAUGGCGCCGAUCCAAAUAUUACGGAUGUCUUUGGAAGGACUGCUCUGCACUACGCUGUGUAUAAUGAAGAUACAUCCAUGAUAGAAAAACUUCUUUCAUAUGGUGCAAAUAUUGAAGAAUGCAGCGAGGAUGAAUAUCCGCCACUGUUCCUUGCUGUGAGUCAAAGAAAAGUGAAAAUGGUGGAAUUUUUAUUAAAGAAAAAAGCAAAUAUAAAUGCCGUUGAUUAUCUUGGCAGAUCAGCCCUCAUACAUGCUGUUACUCUUGGAGAAAAAGAUAUAGUCAUUCUUCUUCUGCAGCACAAUAUUGAUGUGUUUUCUCGAGAUGUGUAUGGAAAGCUUGCAGAAGAUUAUGCCAGCGAGGCUAAGAACAGAGUCAUUUUUGAACUAAUUUAUGAAUAUGAAAGAAAGAAACAUGAAGAGCUUUCUAUAAAUAGCAAUCCAGUGUCUUCUCAGAAACAACCAGCCUUGAAGGCUACAAGUGGCAAGGAAGAUUCUAUCUCGAAUAUAGCCACAGAAAUAAAGGAUGGACAAAAAUCUGGGACAGUGUCUUCUCAGAAACAACCGGCCUUGAAGGGUACAAGUGACAAGAACGAUUCUGUUUCGAACACAGCCACAGAAAUAAAAGAUGAACAAAAAUCUGGGACAGUGUCUUCUCAGAAACAACCGGCCUUGAAGGAUACAAGUGACAAGAACGAUUCUGUUUCGAACACAGCCACAGAAAUAAAAGAUGAACAAAAAUCUGGGACAGUGCUUCCUGCUGUUGAACAGUGUUUAAACAGGAGUCUCUACAGACCGGAUGCUGUUGCACAGCCUGUGACAGAGGAUGAGUUUGCUUUGGAAUCUGAGAUUAUUUCAAAACUAUACAUCCCAAAGAGAAAGAUUAUUUCUCCACGAUCUAUAGAAGAUGUGCUUCCUCCUGUUGAAGAGGCUGUUGACAGGUGUCUCUACCUACUGGACCGUUUUGCACAGGCUGUGACAAAGGAUAAGUUUGCUUUGGAAUCUGAGAAUAUUUCAGAACCAUACUUUACAAACAGAAGGACUAUUUCUCAACAAUCUGCAGAAAAGUUAGAUGCUGCAUGUGGCAUUGACAAAACAGAAAAUGGAACCUUGUUUGAAGACCAAAAUGUUGAUAAGGAAGGAAAAGCACUACCAGCAACUGGACAAAAAGCAAAUGUGUCUCCUGAGCAACCGCCUUUAUUCACGCAUACGGUGAAAGACAGUGAUCACAUUUCAACUAGAUUCUUAGGAAGUAUGGAUUCACUAACUUCCAGUGAAGAAUCUUCUGAGCGACCUCCUUUAUCCACGCUUACUCUGAAAGAGGCAGAUCCCAGUUCAAAAGCAGCCAUGAGAAGGAAGGAUUCACCACCUCCAGGAAAAGUGUCUUCUCAGAAACAACCAGCUGAGAAGGCUACAAGUGACGACAAAGAUUCUGUUUCAAAUAUAGCCACAGAAAUAAAGGAGGGACCAAUAUCUGGGACAGUGUCUUCUCAGAAACAACCAGCUGAGAAGGCUACAAGUGAUGAGAAAGAUUCUGUUUCAAAUAUAGCCACAGAAAUAAAGGAGGGACAACAAUCUGGGACAGUGUCUCCUCAGAAACAAUCAGCCUGGAAGGUUAUAUUUAAAAAGAAAGUUUCUCUUUUGAAUAUUGCCACAAGAAUAACGGGCGGUGGGAAAUCUGGAACAGUGUCUUCUCAGAAACAACCACCCUCAAAGGCUACAAGUGACAAGACAGAUUCUGCUUUGAAUAUAGCUACAGAAAUAAAGGAUGGACUACAAUGUGGGACAGCAGGCCGGAGAUUCUUCAUUUGUAAUAAGUUCUCGGGUGACGCUGAUGCUGCUGGUCUUGGACAUGAUCUUCGCGUGUCUUCUCAGAAACAACCAGCCUUGAAGGCUACAACUGACGAGGAAGAUUCUGUUUCGAAUAUAGCCACAGAAAUAAAGGAUGGAGAAAAAUCUGGGACAGUGUCUUCUCAGAAACAACCAGCCUUGAAGGCUACAACUGACGAGGAAGAUUCUGUUUUGAAUAUAGCCACAGAAAUAAAGGAUGGAGAAAAAUCUGAGACAGUGUCUUCUCAGAAACAACCAGCCUUGAAGGCUACAACUGACGAGGAAGAUUCUGUUUCGAUUAUAGCCACAGAAAUAAAGGACGGAGAAAAAUCUGGGACAGUGUCUUCUCGGAAAAAACCAGCCUUGAAGGCUACAAGUGAUGAGAAAGAUUCUUUUUCGAAUAUAACCAGAGAAAAAAAGGAUGGAGAAAUAUCUAGGACAGUGACUUCUGAGAAACCAGCAGGCUUGAAGGCUACAAGUGACGAGGAAGAUUCUGUUUUGAAUAUAGCCAGAGGAAAAGAGGAUGGAGAAAAAACUAGGAGAGUGUCUUCUCGGAAAAAACCAGCCUUGAAGGCUACAAGUGAUGAGAAAGAUUCUUUUUCGAAUAUAACCAGAGAAAAAAAGGAUGGAGAAACAUCUAGGACAGUGUCUUCUCAGAAACCACCAGCCUUGAAGGCUACAAGUGACGAGGAAGAUUCUGUUUUGAGUAUAGCCAGAGAAGAAAAGGAUGGAGAAAAAUCUAGGACAGUGUCUUCUGAGCAACCACCAGGCUUGAAGGCUACAAGAGAUGAGAAAGAUUCUCUUUUGAAUAUAGCCAGAGGAAAAAAGCAUGGAGAAAAAACUAGGAGAGUGUCUUCUCGGAAAAAAGCAGCCUUGAAGGCUACAAGUGAUGAGAAAGAUUCUUUUUCAAAUAUAACCAGAGAAAGAAAGGAUGGAGAAACAUCUAGGACAGUGUCUUCUCAGAAACCACCAGCCUUGAAGGCUACAAGUGACGAGGAAGAUUCUGUUUUGAAUAUAGCCAGAGAAAAAAAGGAUGGAGAAAAAUCUAGAACAGUGUCUUCAGAGCAACCACCAGGCUUGAAGGCUACAAGAGACGAGAAAGAUUCUCUUUUGAAUAUAGCCAGAGGAAAAAAGUAUGGAGAAAAAACUAGGAGAGUGUCUUCUCGGAAAAAAGCAGCCUUGAAGGCUACAAGUGAUGAGAAAGAUUCUUUUUCAAAUAUAACCAGAGAAAGAAAGGAUGGAGAAACAUCUAGGACAGUGUCUUCUCAGAAACCACCAGCCUUGAAGGCUACAAGUGACGAGGAAGAUUCUGUUUUGAAUAUAGCCAGAGAAAAAAAGGAUGGAGAAAAAUCUAGAACAGUGUCUUCUGAGCAACCACCAGGCUUGAAGGCUACAAGAGAUGAGAAAGAUUCUCUUUUGAAUAUAGCCAGAGGAAAAAAGCAUGGAGAAAAAACUAGGAGAGUGUCUUCUCGGAAAAAAGCAGCCUUGAAGGCUACAAGUGAUGAGAAAGAUUCUUUUUCAAAUAUAACCAGAGAAAGAAAGGAUGGAGAAACAUCUAGGACAGUGUCUUCUCAGAAACCACCAGCCUUGAAGGCUACAGGUGACGAGGAAGAUUCUGUUUUGAAUAUAGCCAGAGAAAAAAAGGAUGGAGAAAAAUCUAGAACAGUGUCUUCUGAGAAACCAUCAGGCUUGAAGGCUACAAGUGACGAGAAAGAUUCUGUUUUGAAUAUAGCCAGAGGAAAAAAGCAUGGAGAAAAAACUAGGAGAGUGUCUUCUCAUAAACAACCAGCCUUGAAGGCUACAAGUGACAAGGAAAAUUCUGUUCCGAAUAUGGCCACAGAAACAAAGGAUGAACAAAUAUCUGGGACAGUGUCUUCUCAGAAACAACCAGCCUUGAAGGCUACAAGUGACAAGAAAGAUUCUGUUUCGAAUAUACCCACAGAAAUAAAGGAUGGACAACAAUCUGGAACAGUGUCUUCUCAGAAACAACUGGCCUGGAAGGCUACAAGUGUCAAGAAAGAUUCUGUUUCGAAUAUAGCCACAGAGAUAAAGGAUGGACAAAUACGUGGGACAGUGUCUUCUCAGAGACAACCAGCCUUGAAGGCUACAGGUGAUGAGAAAGAUUCUGUUUCGAAUAUAGCCAGAGAAAUAAAGGAUGGAGAAAAAUCUGGGACAGUGUCUCCUCAGAAACAAUCGGCCCAGAAGGUUAUAUUUAAAAAGAAAGUUUCUCUUUUGAAUAUUGCCACAAGAAUAACGGGCGGUUGGAAAUCUGGAACAGAGUAUCCUGAGAAUCUGCCCACCUUGAAGGCUACAAUUGAAAAUAAAAAUUCUGUUCUGAAUACAGCCACCAAAAUGAAAGAUGUACAAACAUCCACACCAGCAGAACAAGACUUAGAAAUGGCAUCAGAGGGAGAGCAAAAGAGGCUUGAAGAAUAUGAAAAUAACCAGCCACAGGUGAAAAACCAAAUACAUUCUAGGGAUGACCUUGAUGACAUAAUUCAGUCAUCUCAAACAGUCUCAGAGGACGGUGACUCGCUUUGCUGUAAUUGUAAGAAUGUCAUAUUACUCAUUGAUCAACAUGAAAUGAAGUGUAAAGAUUGUGUUCACCUAUUGAAAAUUAAAAAGACAUUUUGUUUAUGUAAAAGAUUAACAGAACUUAAAGAUAAUCACUGUGAGCAACUUAGAGUAAAAAUUCGAAAACUGAAAAAUAAGGCUAGUGUACUACAAAAGAGACUAUCUGAAAAAGAAGAAAUAAAAUCGCAGUUAAAGCAUGAAACACUUGAAUUGGAAAAAGAACUCUGUAGUUUGAGAUUUGCCAUACAGCAAGAAAAAAAGAAAAGAAGAAAUGUUGAAGAGUUGCACCAAAAAGUUAGGGAAAAGUUAAGAAUCACAGAAGAGCAAUAUAGGAUAGAAGCUGAUGUGACAAAACCAAUUAAACCGGCUCUCAAAUCAGCAGAGGUGGAAUUGAAGACAGGAGGAAAUAAUUCAAAUCAGGUUUCUGAAACUGAUGAAAAAGAAGACCUGCUGCAUGAAAACCGCUUGAUGCAAGAUGAAAUUGCCAGGCUCAGGCUGGAAAAAGACACAAUAAAAAACCAAAACCUGGAAAAGAAAUACUUAAAAGACUUUGAAAUUGUGAAAAGAAAGCAUGAAGACCUUCAAAAGGCUCUAAAACGGAAUGAGGAAACAUUAGCAGAAACGAUAGCCUGUUAUAGUGGACAGCUUGCUGCUCUGACGGAUGAAAACACAACGCUCCGUUCUAAACUGGAGAAGCAAAGAGAGAGCGGGCAAAGACUGGAAACAGAAAUGCAAUCAUACCGUUGUAGACUGAAUGCUGCUCUAUGUGAUCAUGAUCAAAGUCACUCAUCAAAAAGAGACCAAGAGCUUGCUUUCCAGGGCACAGUAGAUAAAUGUUGUCAUUUACAGGAAAAUUUGAAUUCUCAUGUUCUGAUUCUUUCUCUGCAACUUUCUAAAGCUGAGAGUAAGUUCAGAGUCCUCGAAACUGAGCUCCAUUACACAGGAGAGGCUCUGAAAGAAAAGGCUUUGGUUUUUGAACACGUGCAAAGUGAGCUAAAGCAAAAACAGAGUCAAAUGAAGGACAUUGAAAAAAUGUACAAAAGUGGAUACAAUACAAUGGAAAAAUGCAUAGAAAAGCAGGAAAGAUUUUGUCAACUAAAAAAACAAAAUAUGUUGCUUCAACAGCAACUGGAUGAUGCUCGCAACAAAGCUGACAAUCAAGAAAAAGCAAUACUUAAUAUUCAAGCCAGAUGUGAUGCUAGAGUAGAAAACCUUCAAGCUGAGUGCAGAAAGCACCGUCUCUUACUAGAAGAAGACAAUAAAAUGUUGGUGAAUGAAUUGAAUCAUUCGAAAGAAAAAAAAUGCCAAUAUGAAAAAGAGAAAGCAGAAAGAGAAGUAGCUGUGAGACAGCUUCAACAAAAACAAGAUGAUGUCUUAAACAAACGAUCAGCAACAAAAGCUUUGCUGGAUGCUUCAUCGCGUCACUGCAUCUAUUUAGAAAAUGGGAUGCAGGAUUCAAGGAAGAAAUUAGACCAGAUGAGAAGUCAAUUUCAAGAAAUACAGGAUCAACUUACAGCUACUAUAAGAUGUACUAAGGAGAUGGAAGGCGACGCACAAAAGCUUGAAGUAGAAAAUGUCAUGAUGAGAAAAAUUAUUAAAAAACAGGAUGAACAAAUUGAGCGGUUUGAGAAAAUCCUGCAGCAUUCAAGUUUGAUGCUGCAGGUGUUUGAGAGCUAGAUGAAGCAUCCAGCCAAACUAGACUACAUGGAGCUCCACAGUGAUCGUCUUCACCUCCAGCUGUUUGCAUUUACUUCUUCCCUCUAUCCUACAUGUGUUUUCCUUCCCCUUCAGAUAUCAACCUAUGAAUUGCCUCUACCAAAAAGCCUACAAUAUUGACACAAACCUGGGCUAGUAUCCCUUCUAUGUCUUCCAAUAAGUGCUGUCUUAUGCCUGUCAUUGUAUGUAUGACUCUGUACGGGAAUUGCCUGUUUGUUUUUUCAGAUUAUAGCAUACAGUUGUUGAGGGGUGGACUGUAUCAUCUUUAUCUUGUAAUUCCAGUGCUUGUCCUAGUACCUUAGCACAUGGUUGCUGAAUACAUGAAUGAAGAGUGAGAAACCAGAAGCUCUGAUACUUAACUGCCAUGAUAAUGAAUUCAGUGUGCAACUAUGGGCAAAUUAUAUUUAAUAGUAAUUGCAUAUUGUACAUAUUUUUCAUUCUUAUUAACACUGAUAAACUUUUCAACAUAUACUGACUUUCUCUUAGUUAACUGUGAAAUCAUUUAGAUAAAGAAUAUAAUUCUUUUUCAUUGUAACUUCUGAAUUUAAAUCUGAAUCCUCUAUAGCAGGGGUCCCCAACCCCCAGGUCACAGACAGGUCCAUGACCUGUUAGGAACCAGGCUGCACAGCAGGAGGUGAGUGGCAGGCAAGCGAGUGAAGCUUCAUCUGUAUUUCCAGCCACUGCCCGUUGCUCACAUUAUCACCUGAGCUCUGCCUCCUGUCAGAUCAGCAAAGCCAUUAGAUUCUCACAGGAGUGAAAAUCCUAUUGUGAACUGCACGUUCAAGGGAUCUAGGUCACAUGCUCCUUAUGAGACUCUAAUGCCUGAUGAUAUGUCAUUGUCUCCUUUCUCUUCACGAUGGGACCAUCUAGUUACAGAAAAACAAGCUCAGGACUCCCAUUGAUUCUCCAUUAUGAUGAGUUGUGUAAUUAUUUCAUUAUGUAUUACAAUGUAGUAAUAAUAGGAAUAAAGUGCACAAUAGAUGUAAUACGCUUGAAUCACCAUCCUGAAACCAUCCCCCAAACCCCCAUCUGUGGAAAAAUUAUCUUUCACAAAACUGCUGCCUGGUGCCAAAAAGGCUGGGGACUGCUGCUCUAUAGCUUCUGCACUAGAAUCUACUAAUGAGUAAAAUCUAAAUCAAUACCUAGUUUUAAAAGCAUAACAAGAAUAUGUGCUGUCUGGCUGCAGUGGCUCAUGCCUGUAUUCUCAGCACUUUGGGAGGCCAGUGCAGGUGGACCACUUGAGGUCAGGAGUUCAAGACCAGCCUGGCCAAUAUGGUGAAAUCCUGUCUCUACUAAAAACACAAAAAUUAGCUGGGUGUGGUGGUGCAUGCCUGUAGUCUCAGCUACUCGGGAAGCUGAGGUGGGAGAAUCACUUGAACCCGGGAGGCAGAGGUUUCAGUGAGCCAAGAUCAUGCCACUGCACUCCAGCCUGAGCAACAGAGUGACUCCAUCUCAAAUGCAAAACAAAACAGAAAGAAUACGUGCUGACAAAAAAAAUCUAAAAGACAAUAAAAUUGUAUUACUAGGCUGUUAACAUGAUAUUUUGUUUCCCAUUAAAUGUGUGACAUGCAAAAGUAUUUAUUAAAUGAAAAUAUUUUUGUA